AGAGUUUUUCGCUUUCGCUGGCUGUGCUUGCGGAGCACUUUGGGUUUCAUUUGUAAAGGAGCCGGAGCCCCAGGAGUCGAUGGAUGGAGAUGAAAAGGAACUAGAGAGCAGCGAAGAGGGAGGCUCAGCCGAGGAGCGGAGACUCGAGCCGCCGUCCAGCAGCCACUACUGUCUUUACAGCUAUCGCGGAAGCAGAUUGGCACAGCAACGAGGGGACAGUGAGGACGGAAGCCCAAGUGGCACAAAUGCAGAAACUCCCUCUGGUGAUGAUUUCAGCCUCUCCUUGGCAGAUACUAAUCUACCAUCCGAAGUGGAGCCAGAGCUGCGCAGUUUCAUUGCUAAGCGUCUUUCAAGAGGUGCAGUCUUUGAAGGGCUGGGUAAUGUUGCAUCUGUGGAGCUAAAAAUUCCAGGUUACCGAGUUGGUUGUUAUUACUGCCUUUUCCAAAAUGAAAAACUGCUUCCUGAAACAGUAACGAUAGACUCUGAACGUAACCCUUCAGAAUAUGUGGUCUGUUUUUUAGGAGGGUCUGAAAAAGGACUUGAGCUUUUCAGGCUUGAAUUGGACAAGUACAUUCAAGGGCUGAAAAAUAACAUGAAUUGUGAGGCAAGGGGCCUGGAGAGUCACAUAAAAUCCUAUCUGAGCAGCUGGUUUGAGGAUGUUGUAUGCCCAAUCCAAAGGGUUGUUCUUCUCUUUCAGGAAAAGCUUACCUUUCUGCUACAUGCUGCUUUGAGUUACACUCCUGUUGAAGUUAAAGAAUCAGAUGAAAAAACAAAGAGAGACAUUAACAGGUUUCUGAGUGUGGCCAGUCUUCAAGGACUUAUUCAUGAAGGCACCAUGACUUCUUUGUGCAUGGCCAUGACAGAGGAGCAGCAUAAGUCUGUGGUCAUCGAUUGCAGCAGCUCCCAGCCUCAGUUCUGCAAUGCAGGAAGUAACCGGUUUUGUGAGGAUUGGAUGCAAGCUUUUUUAAAUGGUGCCAAAGGAGGUAACCCUUUUCUUUUCCGACAAGUACUGGAGAACUUUAAACUAAAGGCCAUACAAGACACAAACAAUUUGAAGAGAUUUAUCCGACAGGCAGAAAUGAAUCAUUAUGCUUUGUUUAAAUGUUACAUGUUCCUAAAGAACUGUGGUAGUGGAGAUAUACUUUUGAAGAUUGUUAAAGUGGAACAUGAAGAAAUGCCUGAAGCCAAAAAUGUGAUAGCUGUCCUUGAAGAAUUCAUGAAAGAAGCUCUUGACCAAAGUUUUUGAUCAUAUGUUUUGAGAUAAUUGUAUGAUCAAGUUGUAUAUUUAAGUCUUAGUGUUUGAAAUUGCAGUUAUAAUUGUUCAUAGGAUUGCUAUUUAAGAUGAUUUGAAACUCAAUCCAGAUUUUCUUUUUGUAUUUUACCAAUUUAACUUAAAUAAAAAUCUGAAGAACAUCUUCACUGAGUCCUAGAUAGAUAAUGUAUGUGAGAGUUGUGAAAUUUUAGUGUCUCACUGGCCCCAUAAAUUCCACGCUUCAGGAAGUUGUUGCUUAAAAAAUUUCAGAGAUGAUUUUGUUUGUGGCUUUUCUCAGGAAAAGCCUGAGUUUGCUGCAGUAUUUAGCAACUUUUCUUCUCAGAAAAACCAUAAUACUUCCUUUUCAGUGGACUGUAGCUUCUUAAAAAAAAAAAUGUAAUUCUAGUCUUAGAACAGAUUAAUACCACUACACCAGUUCAGAGAUAGAUCUGUGCAUCCUGUGGGUGCUUGAUACAUUUUUUUGUCUAGUUGAUAACGGCAUGGAUGAUAAAGUCAGAUUUUAAGUCAAUAUGCAAAUCCUGAGUAUGUAGAAAAUUAAAUGAGCUUUACAAAUCGAUGCACUAGCUUCAAGAUAAAAUAUUAUCUUUGAGCUGGGCGCAGUGGCUCAAGCCUGUAAUCCCAGCACUUUGGGAGGCUGAGGCGGGCAGAUCAUGAGGUCAGGAGAUCGAGACCAUCCUGGCUAACACAGUGAAAGCCCGUCUCUACUAAAAUACAAAAAAUUAGCCGGGCAUGGUGGCGGGCGCCUGUAGUCCCAGCUACUCUGGAGGCUGAGGCAGGAGAGUGGCGUGAACCCAGGAGGUGGAGCUUGCAGUGAGCCGAGAUCGCGCCACUGCACUCCAGCCUGGGCGACAGAGCGAGACUCUGUCUCAAAAAAAAAAAUAAUUAUCUCUGAGAGAAAGCUACUGCAGAAAUCGCCUUCAGUCACCAUUUCAUUUAUUUGUUCACAGGUAUUUAUGAAGAGCCUGUGUUUUCUUUUAGGUGAAAAUGCUGGAGUUUUAAAACAGUGUUGAGAAAAGAAACAAAGUACAUACAGUUUACAAGCAAACUGUAACAUAAGGAAUGCAAACAGUUUCUUCCUAUUAGAGUUACUCAUUGAUUUUAGUUUUUUGUACAUUUGUUACAAGCCUCAGAUUGUUUUACUCUGAAUCAAUUGAAAGUGCCCUCAGCUAGCCAUUUACAAUUCCCAUGGAAGCCUAUGUAGCUACAUACAUACAAUUGCAAUUUGCUCGGGAUAGCUCUUUAAUAAAUUCAUUUGAUAAUGAUUUUUGCUUAGAAGAACAGAAGUCUUGUGUUCUCACUUCCCUGAGGAUGCUCAGAGGAGCACAAACCCAUAAAACUGAGGAAUCCUCUCUUAAAUGGAUCUAAAUUCACAUUAAGUGCUGAGUUUUAACUUUCAAAAUGACUGACAAUGGCCUUCUGCUUUCUCCUCUACAUAAGCCUCGGGACAUGACUCACAUUUCUUUUCUUUUAAUGAGAAAUACAAUUCAGAAUCUUCAUAAAUGCUUUCAUACGGUUUUAAACUUUAAUAACUUGGAAUGUAGGCAGUAUAGAAAAAAAUCUAAGUAGCAUUUUUCAUAGUAUUAAAGUGAGAGUGGCUGGGCACGAUGGCUCAUGCCUGUAAUCCCAGCACUUUGAGAGGCCGAGGCAGGUGGAUCACCUGAGGUCAGGAGUUCCAGACCAGCCUGACCAAUAUGGUGAAACCCUGUCUCUACUAAAAUUACAAAAAUUAGCUGGGAACUGUGGCAUGUGCCUGUAGUCCCAGCUACUUGGGAGGCUGAGGCAGGAGAAUCGCUUGAACCCGGGAGGCAGAGAUUGCGGUGAGCCGAGAUCGCGCCACUGCAUUCCAACCUGAGUGACAGAGCGAGACUCUGUCUCAAAAAAAUAAAGUCAGGGUGACUAAGGAAAACCAGCAAUUUUAUGACACUGUCCUUGAAUCUGACUGUCUUUUCCCAAUGUAGUUGGUUCCCCACUUGGAAAUCAUUUUUUAAAGUAAGCUACAUUAGCACAUCAACGUUUUAAGUCUGAAAAAAUACUUCAUUUUCAAAUUCAUGUCAUUCAAGAGUCUAUGUUGUAAAUGGCAUUUAAAAGCAAAUGUGUUACCUGCUUCAAAUCAUUUAUGGAUAUAGGCAAGGUGUAAUUACAUAUUCUCUGUGUGGUUGUAUAUAUUUUUGUAAUGUAGGCUCACUACAUUACACAGCUCUAUAUGAUAGUCUUAUUUUAUCUUUUUUUUUUUUUAAUGAAAUGGGGUCUCACUAUGUUGCUCAGACUGGUCUUAAACUCUUGGACUCAAGCAAUCCUCCCACCUUGGCCUCCCAAACUGAGCCACUGCACCCGGCCUCUGGUAGUCUUAUUUUAAAAAAAGUAAGUCUGGGCUGGGUGUGGUGGCUCAUGCCUGUAAUCCCAGCACUUUGGGAGGCCUAGGCGGGCAGAUCAUGAGGUCAGGAGAUCGAGACCAUCCUGGCUAACACGGUGAAACCCCGUCUCUACUAAAAGUACAAAAAAUUAGCCGGGCGUGGUGGCAGGCGUCUGUAGUUCCAGCUACUCGGGAGGCUGAGGCAGGAGAAUGGCGUGAACCCGGGAGGCGGAGCUUGCAGUGAGUCGAGAUCACACCACUGCACUCAAGCCUGGGCGACAGAGCGAGACUCCGUCUCAAAAAAAAAAAAAAAGUCUGACAAACUCUGUAUCACUACUGUAGACAAGGAAAAUGGUGUCAUGGAACUGAAUAUCUUGGUCAUGAGAAGAAACCACAGAGUUCAUGACUAGAAACAUGUACUGUAUUCAAAUUUUAAUAAGCUACUAUCUUGGCUUUUAAAGUUGUUUUUUUUUUUGUUUUUGUUUUAUUUUUUAAGACAGAAUCUCGCUCUGUCACCCAGGCUGGAGUGUGGUGGUGCAAUCUUGGCUCACUGCAACCUCUGCCUCCCAGGUUCAAGUGAUUCUCCUUCCUCAGCCUCCCCAGUAGCUGGGACUACAGGCAUGUGCCACCAUGCAUGGCUAAUUUUUUGUAUUUUUAGUAGAGACGGGGUUUCACCGUGUUAGCCAGGAUGGUCUCGAUCUUCUCACCUUGUGAUCCACCCGCCUUGGCCUCCCAAAGUGCCGGGAUUACAGGCGUGAGCCACUGUGCCCAGCCAGCUUUUAAAGUUUUAAAAAGGAUUUGUUCAGACAUGGAAUAUAUUUGUGUAUAUUACUUGUGUGCUGUACACACAGAGGAAAUGUAUGUUUGUCAUGUAUGAAGAAUGGCUUCAGUUUCUCUGUAAUUAAUUUGUAAUUAUAAUAAUAAAACUUAGCUUCUCAUCAA